AGUGUUGGGGUCCCGCCGUCCUGAGGCUCGAGCUCUUGCGGGUCGAUCGGUCGGCGGGGCCUGCGCGGGGCCCGGGCCCAUGGCGGCGUCGGCGGCUCUGUCUGCGGCGGCGGCGGCGGCAGCCCUGUCUGGCUUGGCGGUUCGGCUGUCGCGCUCGGCGGCGGCCCGAGGCUCAUACGGCGCCUUCUGCAAGGGGCUCACGCGCACGCUGCUCACCUUCUUCGACCUGGCCUGGCGGCUGCGCAUGAACUUCCCCUACUUCUACAUCGUGGCCUCGGUGAUGCUCAACGUCCGCCUGCAAGUGCGGAUCGAGUGAGCGCCGGCGGCGGCGGCGGCCGCGGAGGCCCGGCUGGAGGGGCGACAGUGUCCCCGCCCGCCCCCGGCCGGGUCGCGGGCAUGAAGGACAGCUGGAUCGCGGCGGGGGGCGGAGGUGGGGCGGCCCGGGCCCCUGGACUCUAGACCUACGCCGCCCGGGCACGAAGGCCCAGCCCUGGCCCUGGCCGCGGUCUCAGCCCGGGACCCCGGAUCGCGCAGAAAUGCACUGAACAGGCCCCUACAAUUGGGCUCCAGAAACUACCUGAGCUCGGACUACCUGUUGCCUCACAUUGGCAAAAGAGGGGGAAACCAGAAGGAGGGAAUUCUGCUGCGGCGACUUGACUUUCCCCGCCCCGAGCAGAAAGGCAUUGACGUUUGUAGGCGGUGACCCGCCCCUUCUCUGGCCUUGCCAAGAGUCUCAUCCCUACCCUGGGGCACCUCUGACCCUGGACCUGCUUGGGCAGAGGCAGCGUGAAGGGCCUGAACAAGAGGAGAAGAAGGGCCUUCCUAGUAGAGGCACAGCAUGGACAAAGGCUCACAGGGGUGGGGGUGCCCAGUGAUCGAGUCCUGGCUUGGGAGGGAAGGUCUGAGUUCCCUGGGAACUGAAAUCGGCUAGCAGCACUGUGAGAGAGGUGUAUUUCCCCCUCCUAAUGACAGAGGAAACCGAGGCUUCGGGGAGGGGGGGAUUUGCCCUUGACAUGCAGAUAGGAUGAGGAGGAACUGCGUGUGCCCCUGGGCCUGCAGGCUCCCACACCCCUCCCCAGUCUUCUCCAAGACCUGGCAUGAUGGGAGGAGGGAGGGGAAAGUGAAGAGGGAAGCAUAGGGCUCCUAGGGCACCAAGGGAGAGGGGCCCAAGGGUAGGGAAUCUGGGGAUCUCGCUUUCUUUGGAGCAGUACAGAAGAUCACAGGAAAGAUUAGGACAGACAGCUGAGAUGGCAGACAGGAGAGAUGGGCCCCAGGAUCCCUGGGGAGCCAAGCUUUCCCCCACAGCCUAGCCUCCCCACCCCACCUGGAGCUUCACCAAGGGCUUUUCAGCAGUGAAGUGGCACAAACCUCCCAGUUUGGUGGGCAAGUGGGGCUGAUGGUGGUGUCAUGGCUCCUGGAGACACGACAUAACCAGGAGGGUGAAGGGAUAAACCUGGGGUGGGCUGGGGCUGAGACCCAUGGCAUGACCCCAAUUCUCUCUCCUCAAGCUCGACCCCCCCGCCAUCCCCAGGAUCACACAGGAGAAUCUCAUCCUCACGGCUUGGAUUGGUCCUGGGGGCCCCCGGUUGUGCUGCUAACUGGUGUACAAUGCUCAAGAGCAGCCCAGAGGGGAGCCAGGAAGGGACCCUCGCCCUCACCUGCUAUCCCCAUUUCCGCAUCUCUUGCACUGGUACCCUGAGGGCCACAUUCUCAGUUCCUGGGAUUGAAAACUGCAGCAGUCUGGCCAGCUCCAGGGACAGAGUGAUCCAACCACCUACCACGUACCCUCCUCAGCAGGCCACUGGACCCAGGUCCUGAAUGAAGCUGUCCGCCUGCCUCACCCCAGAAGAGGCUGGACAGUGGCUGCCUCGUGCCCCCUGCAGUCUCCCACAGCCAGGGCCCGAUGGGGUGCCUCCUUGUCCCAAGUCUCCUGAGAACCCCUGACCUUGCUGGCCUCUCUCAUCCGCCCCAACCCUGUCCACCCUUGACCACCUCUGGGGGCCUGUCAGCCUGCUGGUCCCCCCAACAGAUCUCUGGGGGCAGCCUCUGUGGGACAAGAGUGAUACAGAGCUGGAGGAGAAGAGGAGUGAGGGGCCUCCUUGUGUCUGAUGCACAGAUGUGGCCCUUUCAAACCCUGGUGUCACCCUCUGGGUGACUGGAUCCCUAGCUCCAGCCUCUUCCUGGGCCAGCCAGGAAGGGUGGAGGAAAGUUCUUUGCUGAUUGCAUGUGUGAUACAGUGGGGGGUGCCUGAGCCCUCCCCAUGCAAGGGGCUCAUCCUGGGACUCUGGAAGCUGCUUCCCUACUGGGAGAAAUGUGUGUCGGAGCUGCAGGGGUCCCUACCCUCAGAGACCCCCGACUGCAGGGAACCCACCCCAUAAGAGGGUCACGGAUGUCCAUGUCCGCCCACCCCCCGUGGCUUCUGCUGUGGCUAUAUUGGCCUAGAGGGGCUGACUGGGGAGGAGCAGGGCUAAGCCCUCAGCAUUUGCUCCUGUCCCUGCCUUUUCACCCCUGCUGCCUGAAGUGGUAGCCCCGCCUGCUGCUUCUCUACCUCCCCUCCCCACCUCUUCUCUCCCCUACAGGGCCCUUGCUGCGUGAUGGGGUCUCCAUGCACUUUAUUUAUUUGCAGUCUGUUUUCUAGGCGGUGGAGCUUCUAGACACCGACCGGAAUGACAUACGUUUCUGUGUGUGAUUCACUGUGUACUGGUCAGCACAGGCUGGCCAGAGAGAUGUUCUUGUUUCUGGUGUUGUCACGUCUUCUUGUUUUCUCUAAGUUUAAAAAAAAAAAAAAGUCCUUGGUUUAAUACACUAAAAUCCCAA